AACCCUUUCUGAACUUUCACUUUCUAUGUCUACCUCAAAGAAUUGUUGUGAGGCUUGAGAUAAUGCAUUUGUAAAGGGUCUGCCAGAUAGGAAGAUGCUAGUUAUGGAUUUACAAGGUUGUUAAGGCUGUAAGAGUCUAAAACCUACAGUGAAUCACAAUGCAUUUACCCCCACUGACUUGGACAUAAGUGAAAACUAGCCAGAAGUCUCUUUUUCAAAUUACUUACAGGUUAUUCAAUAUAAAAUUUUUGUAAUGGAUAAUCUUAUUUAUCUAAACUAAAGCUUCCUGUUUAUACACACUCCUGUUAUUCUGGGAUAAGAUAAAUGACCACAGUACCUUAAUUUCUAGGUGGGUGCCUGUGAUGGUUCAUUGUAGGUAAGGACAUUUUCUCUUUUUCAGCAGCUGUGUAGGUCCAGAGCCUCUGGGAGAGGAGGGGGGUAGCAUGCACCCAGCAGGGGACUGAACUGGGAAACUCAAGGUUCUUUUUACUGUGGGGUAGUGAGCUGCCUUUCUGUGAUCGGUUUCCCUAGGGAUGUUGCUGUUCCCCUCCUUGCUAUUCGCAGCUACAUACAACGUGGCCAACCCCAGUAGGCUGAUCCUAUAUAUGAUCAGUGCUGGUGCUGACUCUCAAUAGCCCCACCCAAGCUGGCUAUAGGUUUACAGAUACAUUAAUUAGGCAACCUAAAAUAUUGAUGCUGGUGUUGGUGUGACAUAAUGCUAUGGCCAGAACUGAAACUUAGAGUUAUAAUUCAUGUAUUAGGGUUCUCCAGAGGGACAGAAUUAGUAGGAUAUAUGUAUAUAUGAAAGGGAGGUUAUUAGGGAGAACUGGCUCCCACAGUUAGAAGGCGAAGUCGCACAAUAGGCCGUCUGCAAGCUGGGUUAGAGAGAAGCCAGUAGUGGCUCAGCCUGAGUUCAAAAACCUCAAAACUGGGGAAGCUGACAGUGCAGCCAGCCUUCAGUCUGUGGCCAAAGGCCCAAGAGCCCCUGGCAACCAACCCACUGGUGCAAGUCCUAGAUUCCAAAGGCUGAAGAACCUGGAGUCUGAUGUCCAAGAGCAGGAAGAGUGGAAGAAAGCCAGAAGACUCAGCAAACAAGGUAGACAGUGUCUACCACCAUAGUGGCCAUACCAAAGAGGCUACCGAUUCCUUCCUGCUACCUGGAUCCCUGAAGUUGCCCUGGUCUCUGCACCUUCUAAACCUAGUUCUUAAGAGCUUUCCAUUACAUGAGCUGUCUCAAAGCCCUCCAAUAAAUUCUCAGUGUAAGCUUCUGUUGCUUGUGGACAGAAAAUUCUGACAGACCUACCCUAUAAGUGUUACUGUCAGGAUAACAUGAGAACGCACAACAGUAAGUGGUCACUAAGUGUUAGCUACGGUUAUUUUGCCCAAGGUAGCAUGGCUAGUUGAUGCCGGUUGAUGGGGCUUAAACCCAGCUCCCUCAUCUUCCAGGCCUCUGUACUCCCUAUUCCACUAAACUACCUCUCAGGUUUAUUUUUUUAAAUUCUUACUCUGCAAGUACAUAGGACCACAUUUACCUGGGAAAACAAGAAUAAAGGCUGCUCUGCAUUUUUUAGAAACUUUUUUGAAAGGGAGAUGGGAAUGCCUGCACCCCCAAGUCCAGACCAACACAAUGGUUAAUUGAGAUGAAUAAUAAAGGAAAGACUGUUCUGGGCUUCCCAGAAUAGCUUGGUCCUUAAAUUGUGGCACAAACAACCUCCUGUCAGAGCCAGCCUCCUGCCAGGAAGAGGGGUAGGAGACUAGAGGCCGUGUGUGCAGCCUUGCCCUGAAGGCUAGGGUGACAAUUUGGAGGCUGUCCAAACACCCUGGCCUCUAGAGCUGGCCUGUCUAUUUGAAAUGCCGGCUCUGAUGCUAAUCGGCGACCCUCAGGCAAGUUACUUAACCUUACAUGCCUCAGUUUUCUCAUCUGGAAAAUGAGAACCCUAGGUUUAGGGUUGUUAGAAAAGUUAAAUGAGUUAAGACAAGUGCCUGGGACACAGUAGCCUCUUGUGUGUGUUUAUCAUUAUGUCCUCAGCAGGUCGUAGAAGCAGCUUCUCAGGUGUGAGGCUGGCGCGAUUAUCUGGAGUGGGUUGGGUUUUCUAGGAUGGACCCCCUGCUGCAUUUUCCUCAUUCAUCCACCAGGGCUUAAUGGGGAAUCAAGGAAUCCAUGUGUAACUGUAUAAUAACUGUAGCCACACUCCAAUGACCACCUACUAGUUGUCCCUGGCACUGCUUAUACAUAUGUCCAUCAAAUCAAUCCUAUGAAGUAGAUACUGUCUUCAUUUUAUAGAUCAGAGACAAUUGGGGUUCAGAGAGCUGAUGUGAUUUUCCCAGGGUCACAGAGAGUCCCAGAUUCAGGCACAACUCUUGUAUUCCAAGACACAACCACUACAUGUCCAAAGGCUGCCCAGAGCCACCGGGCACGGCAAAUUGUGACAUAUCCCUAAAGAGGCUGAGCACCUGGUCAGGAUCUGAUGGCUGACAGUGUGUCCAGAUGCAGAGCUGGAGUGGGGGAGGGGAAGGGGGGCUCCUUGGGACAGAGAAGGCUUUCUGUGCUUUCUCUGAAGGGAGCAGUCUGAGGACCAAGGGAACCCGGCAAACAGCACCUCAGGUACUCCAGGCCCUCCUGGCUGGAGAGGGCUGUGGCAAUGGAAAAUUAGUGCCAACUGCAAUGAGUCAGCCUCGGUUAAAUAGAGAGUGAAGAAUGCUGGACAGGAACCUCCACCCUCAUGUCACAUUUCUUCAGUGUGACCCUUCUGGCCCCUCUCCUCCUGACAGCGGAACAAUGACUGCCCCGAUAGGUGAGGCUGGAGGAAGAAUCAGUCCUGUCCUUGGCAAGCUCUUCACUAUGACAGUAAAGGCUCUCUGCCUGCUGCCAAGGCCUGUGACUUUCUAACCUGGCCUCACGCUGGGUAAGCUUAAGGUAGAGGUGCAGGAUUAGCAAGCCCACCUGGCUACCAGGCCGACAGCUACAUCUUUCAACUGACCCUGAUCAACGAAGAGGGACUUGUGUCUCUCAGUUGGUUCCAAAUGAAACCAGGGAGCAGGGGCGUUAGGAAGCUCCAACAGGAUGGUACUUAAUGGGGCAUUUGAGUGGAGAGGUAGGUGACAUAGUGCUUUGGAGCCCAGGGAGGGAAAGGUUCUGCUGAAGUUGAAUUCAAGACUGUUCUUUCAUCACAAACUUGAGUUUCCUGGACAUUUGUUUGCAGAAACAACCGUAGGGUUUUGCCUUAACCUCGUGGGUUUAUUAUUACCUCAUAGGGACUUUGCCUCCUGACAGCAGUUUAUGGGUGUUCAUUGUGGCACUUGAGUUUUCUUGCAUACUUGUUAGAGAAACCAAGUUUGUCAUCAACUUCUUAUUUAACCCCCUGGCUAUAACUUCAUGGAUUAUGUUAUAAUUAAGCCAUCCAGAGUAAAAUCUGUUUAGAUUAUCUUGGAGUAAGGGGGAAAAAAUCUGUAAUUUUUUCUCCUCAACUAGAUAUAUACAUAAAAAAUGAUUGUAUUGCUUCAUUUAAAAAAUAUAACGCAAAAUCUCUUUUCCUUCUAAGGGCCUUUAAUAUGUAAUAACAAGAGCUAAUGUUGAACACAAGCCAUUGCCAGGUACUUAAACUGUCUCACUUAGUCUUGCCAACCUAAGCAAGUAGAUGCCAUUACUAUUCCCAUUAUAUUGAUGAAAAAAUGAGGUUGAGAAAGGUUCAGCCGCACAGCCAAAUACAUAGUGGAUCCAGGGUUUGGUCCCAAGUCUUGAGUCCAAAACCCUGGUUCUUACCAUUACUGUGGUUCUGUAGGGGUGAAAAAAUUUUUCUUCUAAUCUCUUAGGUUCAGAGCCUGGGGCCUGAGAAUUAAACUGACAAAGACAGAUUAACAGAAGACAAAGUUUAUUACGCAGUAGUGGAUGAAAAAUCAGACACUGAUUUUCUCAGACUUCUUUGCUGUGGGCGCGGCCAGUGAGGCAAUGAGGUAAGUCUGCUGGUGCAGGGGCCAGGUUUCUAGGAAAUACUUUUCUCCCUCAUGGGAGAAAGAGAGGAAGCCUGAAGUAAGCUUUCUUCUGCAGCCCUGGCCCGCUGCCUGUUCUGGAUGAGGGUAUGCUGGGAUAUGACAACGGAAGCCAGCGGGGUCGCAGAGCAAGAGCGAGGCGGUGGGCGGAGUCGAGGGACGGGAGGCGAGGCGAGGCGAGCCAGGGGGCGUGGCUUUCUAACUGCGGGGUGCGGCCAGCCGAGGUGGGCGGGGCCGCGUUCCGGGACGUGGUCGUCCGGGCUUUGGAACCCCGCCUGUUAGGGGCCGGGCUGAGGCGAAAGGGUGGGGCCGCGCUCCAUCGGGGCGGGGCUUGUGGAACCUCGAAACCCCGGCGACUCGGGGCCUGAGCGCGCGUCUCCCGGCGCGGGGUUCCUCCCACGCAGACCCUCAUUCAAACGAUGCCAAAGGGGCGGCGCGGCAGCCACAGCCCCACCAUGAGCCAGCGGUCGGCUCCGCCCCUCUAUUUCCCGUCCCUGUACGACCGCGGCAUCUCCUCGUCCCCGCUCAGCGACUUCAACAUCUGGAAGAAGCUCUUCGUGCCGCUGAAGGCGGGCGGGGCGCCAGUGGGCGGGGCGGCGGGGGCCCGGUCCCUGUCCCAGGCGCUCCCCGCCCCGGCGCCCCCGCCCCCGCCACCACCCGGCCUGGGUCCCUCCAGCGAGCGCCCCUGGCCCUCGCCCUGGCCCUCCGGCCUGGCCUCCAUCCCCUACGAGCCUCUGCGCUUCUUCUACUCACCGCCGCCGGGGCCUGAGGUGGUUGCCUCGCCCCUGGUCCCCUGCCCCUCGACCCCCAGGCUCGCCUCUGCCUCCCACCCGGAGGAGCUCUGCGAGCUGGAGAUCCGGAUUAAGGAGCUGGAGUUGCUCACCAUCACUGGGGACGGCUUCGACUCCCAGAGCUACACAUUCCUGAAGGCGCUAAAAGACGAAAAGUUACAAGGACUGAAGACCAAGCAACCUGGAAAGAAGUCGGCCUCUCUCUCCUGAGGAGCUGCCUACCAGAGCUUGGGCAGCCACCUCCUUAGGUGUUAGUGCUUAGAUAAUGUGUCCCAUUUGUUGUCAUUUCAAAGAUGGUUAUUUUCUGUUCUGUAUUUACCGCUGUUCUUGUUGCUACCAGCAUGUACUUCACAUACAGUGCCCACUUUGUGUGGUAAA